UUACAGGCAUAAGCCACCCUGCCUGACCAAAAACAUUUCUUCUUGUUUUGAGAAGCUUCUGGGCUCCAGAGACAGAAGAUGAGGAAGUUUUAUUUUCCAAUCCAGCAAAUUCUAGGCUCUCAAUAUUCUCAGUUCUUUGCAAACUGUGCAGUUCUUUCUUCUGCAUAUCUCUCAUGUUACUUUAUCAUAGUUAGUUUAUCAAACUAUUCAGCUAACAGCGAAAUGGCCUCCCAUAGACUUCACAAACUCCAUUCACAGCAUCAACUUGGCAGCUCAAUCUGCUUGGCUUCUCUGAUUGAUGGCUCUUCUCUGAUCCUCCAACUCCUUCUUCUAGACCUUCACCUCUCUAGAUCUUCCCAUGGUUUCAUUAUGGUCUAAUUCUUGUAACUCCUGUUCCCUAACACUCAGGUGACUUUGCUGUCCUGACUGAACCUUGCUUAAUACAGAAAUUUAUACUCAGAAAUGCAAUGCAAUAAUAAAAACCUAGAAUGUGGCACUGACUUUAGGAUCAGGUAGCAGGCAAAGGCUGAACGGGUGUCAAGAAGCCUGUUGGUGGAGGCUGGAACAAUGGGGGAAAUUGCUACUAGAAUCUGGGAAAAAUAUGACCCAUGUCAUGUAUUAAUACAUGUAGACUAACUGGCAAAAAUAUGACCAUUGGUAACAACUGGUAUAUCUAAGGAGAUUUCUAGGCAUUGUUUUGGGGAUGUGAAUUGGCCUCUGAACAAGGAGUUCCUGGGGUGGUAUAUGGGAAGCUGUUAUCUGAAUAGCUACUGUCUCUGAUGCUUAGCCAACAGUGGUUUGAGGCCACUGUUGGUCAGCAAGGCCAGCGUUCGGGAAGAAAGCCAGACAUAGAGCAGAGGACAAAGUGGAUUCUGACAGACAUUUCUGAAUCUGUCUCUGAGUGUGAAAAGAUCAUGAAAGUCAUCAAAGUGUAUUCAUCAUGCCUCACUCUGCUUUCCAAAAUCUUGUUCCAUUUUUGUCCCGCUCCUAACCCAAACCAUGUAGAGAAAAGAUUUCUGGGAAACACUGUUACUACCGUAACCAAAUUGACUCAGUAAAAUCUGUCACAGAACCACAUCAAAUAUUGAAAAUUUAAAAUUGACAACAGUGUGAAAUUUGUUUUUAAAUCAUUUUUAUUAUAAAAUAUGCAUAAGAUGUACCACGUAAAGCAAUUUCAAGUGUACAGUUCAGUGACAUUAAGUACAUUCACAUUGUUAUGAAACCUGUCACCACCAUCCACAUGUAGAACUUUUUUCAUCUUCCCAAACUGAAACUUCUCUAACCAUUAAACAGUAACUCCCCAUUCCCUCUCCCCUUUUAGCCCCUGCCAACCACCACUAUCCUUUCUCUUAUGAAUUUCACUACUGUGGGUACCCUUUGUAAGUGGUACUUUUGUGACUGGUUUAUUCCACUUAGCAUAAUGUCUUCAGGGUUCAUCCAUGUGUCAGAAUUUUUUCAUUUUUAAUACUAAAUAAUAUGUAAUAUAUGUUUUUAUGUAAAUUUUAUAUAAUCAUAAAACAACAUAAUUUUAAUAUUUUAUGUUUAUACAUUUAAUACUUUAAUGUUUUAUCUGAAUAAUUUAAUUCUGUAUGUAAUAAUUGCUUUUUAAUACUAAAUAUUCCAUUUUAUGUAAAAAGCACAUUUUGUUUAUUCAUUCAUCUGUUGGACACCUGAGUGACUUCUGCCUUUUGGCUGUUGUGAACCUGCUUUCAGUUAUUUCAGAUAUGUACCAAAAUAGGAAUUGAAGAAAUAGGAAUAAGAAUAGGAAUUGCCGGAUCAUAUGAAAAUUCUGUUUAAUUUUUUAGGGAACUGCCAUACCGUUUUCUGUAGCAGCCACACCAUUUUCCAUUCCCAUGAGCAAUGCAGCAAUGUCUCUUAAGGUUUCCAAUUUCUCCACAUUCUCACCAACACUUGUUACUUUCUGGGUUUUUUUUUUUUCCAAGAUGGAGUCUCACUCUUGUUGCCCAGGCCGGAGUGCAGUUGCGUGAUCUUGGCUCACUGCAACCUCCGCCUCCCGGGUUCAAGCAGUUCUCCUGCUUCAGCCUCCGGUGUGCUACCACGCCUGGCUAAUUUUUGUAUUUUUAGUAGAGACAGGGUUUCACCAUGUUGGCCAGGCUGGUCUUGAACUCCUGACAUCAUGAUCUGCCCGCCUUGGCCUCCCAAAGUGCUGGGAUUGCAGGCCCACCUCUGUUGUUUGUUUUUGAGACAGGAUCUUGCUGUGUCACCCACGCUCAGGCUGGAGUGAAGUUGCAUAAUCCUGGCUCACUGCAACUUCCACCUCCUGGACUCAAGCCAUUUUCCUGCCUCAGUUUCCCAAGUAGCUGGGACUACAGGUACAAGUGCGUGCCGCCACGCUAAUUUUUUAUAUUUUUUUUGUAGAUAUGGGGUUGGCCAGGCUGGUUUCAAACUCCUGAGCUCAGGCGAUCAGCCCGCCUCAGCAGCCUCCCAAAGUGGUGUGGUGGGAUUAUAGGCGUGAGCCACUGCGCCUUGCCAGAUUUUUUGUUUUAGAAAAUAGCCUUCCUAAUGAUUGUGAAGUGGUAUCUUGUGGUUUUGAUUUGCAUUUUUCUAAUGAUUAGUGAUGUUUAGCAUCUUUUCAUGUGCUUAUCGGUCCCUUGUAUAUUUUCUUUGGUGAAACGUCUGAAUAUUCAAGCCUUUUGCCCAUUUUUUAGUUGGAUUGUUUUUUGUUUGUUUUUCAGUUUGUAGGAUUUCUUUAUAUACUCUGGGUGUUAACUCCUGAGAUAGAUAUUUGCAAAUAUUUUCUCCUAAUGUGUAGGUUGUCUUUUCAUUCUGUUGAUAGUGUUGUUAUUGUUUCUACUGAGAGGUGUUUUUUUUGUUUGUUUUUUUGUUUUUUUGUUUUUUUUUGAGACAGAGUCUCACUCUGUUGCCCAGGCUGGAGUGCAGUGGUUUGAUCUCAGCUCACUGCAACCCCCACUUCCAGGGUUCUAGUGAUUCUCCUGCCUUAGCCUCUGAGUAGGUGGGAUUACAGGCGUACGCCACCACGCCCGGAUAAUCUUUGUAUUUUUAGAAGAGACAGGGUUUCGCCAUGUUGGCCAGGCUGGUCUCAAACUCCUAACUUCAAGUGAUCCACCCACCUCAGCCUCCCAAAGCGCUAGGAUUACAGGCAUGAGCCACUGCUCCUGGCCUUAUAUGCCAUCUUGAGAAGGCUAAGGGAUGCCCGAAUAGCUAGUAAAACAUUAUUUCUGGGUGUGUCUGUGAGGGUGUUUGUGGAAGAGGUUAGUAUUUAAAUCAGUAGACUGAGUAAAGAAAGAUCCGCCCUCACCAGUGUGGGCCAGCAUCAUCCAAUCAGCUGAGGGCCUGAAUAAAACAAAAAGGUGGAGGAAGGGAGAAUACUGCCUCUCCUUGAGCUGAGACAUUCAUUUUCUCUUUUCCUUGGACAUCAGAGCUCCUGUUCUGGCCUUUGGACGCUGGUAAUACUGCCUCACCUCCACUUCUGGUUCUUAGUUAGGCCUUUGGACUCUGACUGGAUUACAUUAUAAGCUUUCUGUGAGACAGUUCUUAUAAUAAAUCUCUUCAUAUGCAUAUGUAUGAGAAGAGUUUAUAUAUAUGUAAUUGUUUCUGUUUCUCUGGAAAACCUGAACUAAUACUUUGUUCAAAAGUUGAGGCAAAAUAAAAACGUUUCCAGAUAAGCAAAUACUGAGAGAAUUUGUUAGCAGGCUUGCCUUACUAAAGGAAGUACUUCAAGCUGAAAUGAAACGCUAUGGUACCAGAUGGUAACUUGAAGAAAAAGAAGAGCAGAAGUUAAUUUCAGAGAUGUUCUCAAAUAGUGAUGAAGCUGUAAUCAAUAAAAAACUUCCCAAAGAACUCCUGUUACGGAUAUUUUCUUUUCUAGAUGUUGUUACCCUGUGCCGCUGUGCUCAGGUCUCCAGGGCCUGGAAUGUUCUGGCUCUGGAUGGCAGUAACUGGCAGCGAAUUGACCUAUUUGAUUUCCAGAGGGAUAUUGAGGGCCGAGUAGUGGAGAAUAUUUCAAAACGAUGUGGGGGCUUUUUACGAAAGUUAAGUCUUCGUGGAUGUCUUGGAGUGGGAGACAAUGCAUUAAGAACCUUUGCACAAAACUGCAGGAACAUUGAAGUACUGAAUCUAAAUGGGUGUACAAAGACAACAGACGCUACAUGUACUAGCCUUAGCAAGUUCUGUUCCAAACUCAGGCACCUUGACUUGGCUUCCUGUACAUCAAUAACAAACAUGUCUCUAAAAGCUCUGAGUGAGGGAUGUCCACUGUUGGAGCAGUUGAACAUUUCCUGGUGUGACCAAGUAACCAAGGAUGGCAUUCAAGCACUAGUGAGGGGCUGUGGGGGUCUCAAGGCCUUAUUCUUAAAAGGCUGCACGCAGCUAGAAGAUGAAGCUCUCAAGUACAUAGGUGCACACUGCCCUGAACUGGUGACUUUGAACUUGCAGACUUGCUUGCAAAUCACAGAUGAAGGUCUCAUUACUAUAUGCAGAGGGUGCCAUAAGUUACAAUCCCUUUGUGCCUCUGGCUGCUCCAACAUCACAGAUGCCAUCCUGAAUGCUCUAGGUCAGAACUGCCCACGGCUUAGAAUAUUGGAAGUGGCAAGAUGUUCUCAAUUAACAGAUGUGGGCUUUACCACUCUAGCCAGGAAUUGCCAUGAACUUGAAAAGAUGGACCUGGAAGAGUGUGUUCAGAUAACAGAUAGCACAUUAAUCCAACUUUCUAUACACUGUCCUCGACUUCAAGUAUUGAGUCUGUCUCACUGUGAGCUGAUCACAGAUGAUGGAAUUCGUCACCUGGGGAAUGGGGCCUGCGCCCAUGACCAGCUGGAGGUGAUUGAGCUGGACAACUGCCCACUAAUCACAGAUGCAUCCCUGGAGCACUUGAAGAGCUGUCAUAGCCUUGAGCGGAUAGAACUCUAUGACUGCCAGCAAAUCACACGGGCUGGAAUCAAGAGACUCAGGACCCAUUUACCCAAUAUUAAAGUCCACGCCUACUUCGCACCUGUCACUCCACCCCCAUCAGUAGGGGGCAGCAGACAGCGCUUCUGCAGAUGCUGCAUCAUCCUAUGACAAUGGAGGUGGUCAACCUUGGCGAACUGAGUAUUUAAUGACACUUCUAGAGCUACCGUGGAGUCUCUCCAGUGGAAGCAACCCCAGUGUUCUGAGCAAGGGUUACAAAGUGAGGGAGGGCAGUGUCCAGAUCCCCAGAGCCACACAUACAUACACAUACACACCCUUACCCCCAUCCACUCUAGCUUUGUGACCAUGGGACUGAAGUUUGUGAUGGCUUUUUUAUCAAGUAGAUUGGUAAAAUUUAACCAUUCCUGUUGAGGUGCCCAUAAGAAAAUCAUAGGCCAAGAUAGGGAGGGGCAUUCCAGCAAACCCCGUGUUAAUGCUACUGUGGUUUUUAAAUUUUUGUCUAGGGGUUUCUUUGGGGAUUUUAGAACAGCAUCUGCUGUCCUCCGGGGUCAAGAAAAGCAUGGAAAGACAAUAUAUGAUGUACCCAGGGACCAGAAAGAAAAUUUCUUUGCAUCUUAGAAAUGGUAGACAUUCAUUGUGACUAAAGAGCUUCUAUGCUUCCUUGUUUCCAUGCCAACAUGCUGAGCAUGCUCACAAAGAAGGCUCGUCCAUUCCUCCUGUGUUUUAGUAUUUGGCCCAGAGGUUUCCUAAAUGGUUGCCUUGAAAUCACUGUGGUCCAAAUGUAAUUCUUACACACUCAAAUUAUCACUGUCUGUAGCACACUUGUGCACCUGUCUUACAUUCUCUGUUGCUCCCCCCCACACUCUUGCUCAGUCUGUCACCUGUUCAGUCUGCUUACUCACUCAAUUGUUACCCUUUUGCUGUUGUCGUGUUUACAGUUUGCAUUUUGAAUGAUUAGUUGGGAUUACCAAACAUUUUUUAAAAAGAUAUUAUCAAUAAAUAUUUUUUUAAUUCUAAAUUUUACCAUUAGGGGACCCUGCCUGAAUCUUUGCCAACCUGCAAGGAAACUCUAAUGAAAGCAAGAAAAGUUAUGAGAAGAAACUGUUUUGAUGAAAACAGAUGCUACCUUUUGGUUUCUAUUUUAUCUUCUGAUAUGUGAUAAUUCGCAUGGUAUCCCCAAUAUUCCCCCUACAUAUUCUUCCUUCUGUCAGACUCCACCAACUGUAUCAUAAGGAAAGAGAGAGAUGUAUUAUUAGGAAAGAGUGAAAAUGAUAAAUCACAAAACAGAGCCUGAAAGUCCCCAACACCCAAGUUCAGACAUUAAUGAUUAAUGUUAUUAUAUAUUUACUGAAAUCUAGGAGUGAUCAGUGGCAUCUCUGACCUAUGAGGUUGUUUUAACAGGAAUGCCACUAGAGGAGCUGUGUAUUCUAGCCAGUCUGUUUCUCUCUUUUCCCCCAUUUCAGCCUUUCAGGGAUACAAGAAUGGCUCUAUAACAGCUGGUCAAUUGUAUGUCAGUGUUAAUGGAUUCAUAUCUAGUGUUGGCACCCCAAAGGGCCAGAACCUUCCCAUAACCUGUCAGUCAUCUCUCUUUUCUGCCCCAGUCUUUUUUUUUUUUUUUUUUUUUUUUUAAGACGGGUUCUCACUCUUGCCCAGACUGGAGUGCAGUGGUGCGAUCUCGGCUCACCGCAACCUCCACUUCCCAGGCUCAAGCGAUUCUCUUGCCUCAGCCUACCGAGUAGCUGGGAUUACAGGCAUGCACCACUACUGCCUGGCUAAUUUUUGUAUUUUUAGUAGAGAUGGGGUUUCACAUGUUGGCCAGCCUGGUCUUGAACUCCUGACCUCAAAUGAUCCACCUGCCUCAGCCUCCCAAAGUGCUGGGACUACAGGCAUGAGCCACCAUGCCCGGCCCUGUUCAGACUUCUGAAUGAAGUAUGAAUGUAGCCAGGUGAAGCAUUGAGGCAGCUGAAAGAGAACACUGAGAGGAAGUAAGGGGUUUAGUGUCUCUGCUUAGCCUGGGCACUAGAACUGAGGGAGGAAUUUAGUGUCCAGGACUCAAGAGUCCAAGAAGAAGCACCCUCUGUCUUCCCAAAAAAUCAGAGGAUAAAGGAAGUAAAAUGAGUUUUUAAAGCAUAAGAAGAAAAUUUCUAAACCCCAAGAUUAGAAACCCAGUGUGAUUUUUAGUAGGGUGAUUUUGGCGGGGGGUGUCCUUUGAGACAUUAAUGUGCAAUCCAUCAUAAUAUUAAUCUUCUAUAUGAUCCAGACUAUUAAAAGGCUUGUUUUAUUUAUUUAUUUUAUUUUAUUUUAUUUUUUUAGAGAUGGGGUCUCGCUAUCUUGCCCAGCCUGGACUCAAACUCCUGGGCUCAAGCCUUCCUCCCACCUCAGCCUCCCAAGUAGCUGGGACUACAGGUGUGUGCCACUGUACCCAGCUUAAGAGGUUUGUUUUAAUGCUGCAGUUGCUGAUUAUACCAGCAUAUAUAAGAAUAAAGUCUGAUUUAUUUAUCCAUUGAUUUAGAAGGCAAUUGGAUGAAAGGGUCUUAGAAGUCUAUACUAUCCAUUAAUAUUUAUCAUAUUAAAUUUAUUUUAAAUCCUGUUUUAUUGUGCCGCUUUAAAAACGCAGAUUACUUGUUUAUUCAUUCCCCUUUCCCCUUAUUCUCUUUCAGAUUACCUUAUAAGGAAUAUAGUUUUUAACAUGAAACUCAGUUUCUUGUCUGUACCCCUACACAUAAAAAUACAUACGUGCAUACACACAUACUUCCAGAUGUGGUUAAUAAUAUUCAGAUCCCUAGGUUACUCAAACAAAACUAAAGGAGAGAACUAUUUAGGGGCCAUCUGCUUUAAAGUUUAAGGUGUUUUGUUGUUGUUUUAGUGCCUGUACAAAUUGACCAUAAAACCCAGAUUGAUUAGUGAGUGUGGAUUUGAGUUGCCUAAGUUGAGGCUAUUAAGGUACUUCUUUACUUAAAAGAUAAGUUUAAAAGACUCUAUUCAUCAGUUCAUGAUGAUCUUGGAAAUGCUGUUUCUCUGCUCAAAGGAUAUACCCACAGGCAGGUCCAUGGGGACUUGCUCUGGUGAUCUCUGCUAUUAAGGCAAAUUCCAGCCUGUUUGUGCCAAGAACAGAGUCAAGUGAGAGAGAAUGAAGACUCAGAGAUGUGCAGCACUGGCUUGUAUGUUGUCAGGCAGAAGCCUUGUUCCUUUCUCAAGAAAACUUCAGGCCUAUCAAGCUUGGAAGGAAAUACAUUUUUUUAUGCUGAUUUGCAGCCUACACCAGCUGAUGAAUAUGCUAGGACUUUGAGAGAACACAAAGCAUGGUAAGUUUUGGUCAGGUGGAAAGGAGCCUGACAUCUGAACAUAAUGCUUCCUCUCUCAACAUCUGGGAUACUUUUGAAAAUUCAGUAAGGCUUAAUGUAGGAAAAAUUCUUUACAGGAAAAGCUAAUUGAUCUGUUUGUCUAACCUCAUAGCCACUCCAAAAUAUGCCUUUUAUAAUGGAAAAAAACAGUGAACAGAGAGAAGAGAUUUGGGGAUAAGUUAGAAGGUACCCUCAAAACUACUGCCGUAAACCUACAGGUGGGCAAGGAGGAAUUACUGUAGUGUCUCUGGAGAAAGUUCUUGAACAUCCAAAUCAUCUCUUUUCUAAGCAGUUUUUCCCCUAAUCUCAUACCUUACAUCUUCCAGCAUCAUUUGCUACAUCAAUGUCUUUUCAUCCUCUUCAUCAGCCCCAUUGAGCUGACUCCAGCUUAUUUUUGCACUGAUUUCCACCAUUUCCUUCCCACACCCAUCCUUUCCCUCUAUUUAAAGCCUCCAUCUCACCCUCAGUAAUGCUGCUGAUUUACUCUCAGAUGUCUCAAGUCUAGCUUCCUUUUUGAAUCCUUCUCCUACUCCAGGGGCUGUCAAAGGCAGCCUUAAAGUUCAGUGACUGUUAGGUGGCUCAGGCCAUUUUUCAUUGGGUGGUCUUUGGUGUUUGCAUACUGAAUUUGAAUUCAGUUUAAAAGCAAACUGUUGGAUAUGAGGAAGAAAGGGAUAUGGCCUUAGCCCUUUUUCCAAUAUUUGGAAUAUGAAAGCAUAUUGUGCUUUGUGUAAAAAAUGUUUUCUUCUCCUAUUCUGCUCUUGUCUUUACUGAAGGUAAAAGUAUUCCUUAAGUAGCUUUUGCAAAUUUCUAGUCUGAUUUCCACAUUCAUUAAGUUGAUUUAGCAGACAUGUAAGUCAGAAGUUUCACAUAUCCCUUGUAUCAAACAUUUUAUAGGGAAACCUAGUAAAUUUAUGAUGCUUCAUUUUGGGCUUUCCAGACUAUUUGAGUUAUUCAAGAUAGCCAUAAUGUUUUAGUAGCGACAUUCUUUUAUUACUUCUAAUUGCCUUGUAAAAUGCAUUGUUAUGGCCCGGCACGGUGGGUGGAUCACAAGGUCAGGAGUUCAAGAACAGCCUGGCCAAGAUGGUGAAAUGCUGUCUCUACUGAAAAUACAAAAAUUAGCCAGGUGUGGUGGCAGGUGCCUGUAAUCCCAGCUACUCGGGAGGCUGAGGCAGAGAAUUGCUUGAACCCGGGAGGUGGAGGUUGCAGUGAGCUGAGAUCGCACCACUGCACUCCACCCUGGGCGACAGAGUGAGACUAUCUCAAAAAAAAAGAAAGAAAGAAAGAAAAAAAUGCAUCGUUACUAGUUUGAUAGCCCACUAAUGCCAUGGGGGACUAAACAAAAUAUGUGAUGAAACCUGUCUUGGUUUGAAGUUGUUAGAAAGUGUGAGAGUGUCACUGGAAAGAAGAGAGUGGCUUCCUGCCUGCUUGUUUAGUCAGCAUGUCCUUAGGUGACUGUGUUGUUGGGAGAAGAGCACUCAUGGGUCAUGGGUGACCCUUGGCCAUUUUAUGUUUAUUGUGCUGAAAGUCACAGGCGGCUCAUGCCAGUUGCUACCAGUGAGAGGAGGGGUUUAAAGGAAAUUGCUCUAUUUUGCCUUAUUCCUCCUUAUGUGUAUGAUUUAAGGGUAGGCUUUUAUCCUGGUUGUAUCUCCUGGCUGACAGACUUUCUCAAUCAUAUGUUUGAGCUCUGAAGCAUUUUACAAAAAGAUUGCCUCUCUAUCUGCCUGCCAAUCCUAGAAUCUUUAGCCACCUCAAACCCAGGCACUGUGAAUUAGCCAAGUCCUGUUUGAGAAGAAAUGUAGGAUGUUUGGUUGGAAUUCUUGAGACAGAACCUCUCUCCCCAUUAAUGAUGUUGUACCAAAGAAUUCUAAAGCAGUAAAAGGAUAAUGGGGAAAAAUGGAGUCACAGCCUUUCCUCGCCUAUAUUUCUUUUUUUUUUUUUUUUUUUUGACAUGGAGUCUCGCUCUGUCACCCAGGUUGGAGUGCCAUGGCACAAUCUCAGUUCACUGCAACCUCUGCCUCCUGGGUUCAAGUGAUUCUUCUGUUUCAGCCUCCCAAGAGGCCAGGAUUACAGGUGCCCACCACCACGCCCAGCUAAUGUUUGUAUUUUUCAUAGAGAUGGGGUUUUGCCAUGUUGGCCAGGCUAGUCUCGAACUUCUGACCUCAAGUGGUCCACCUGCCUUGGCCUCCCAAAGUGCUGGGAUUACAGGUGUAAGCCACCGCACCUGGCCAGUUUCUAUCAUAAAUUUUAAAUGUAAGAUUGGAAGAUACAGAGAGCUGUAUAAAAUCAUACCAGUAGGGUAUAAUUAGCCCAGGUAGUUUAGGAAUAAAAUUGGGUUGUAUCCGAGUGCCCUAACUUGACAUUUUGAUUCUCCAGCAAAGAACAUAGGUUACUAGGUUACUAACCUUGCCUUCUCACUUGGGAUAAACUUUUUUUUUUUUUCUUGUUGCCCAGGCUGGAGUGCAAUAGUGAGAUCUCGGCUCACCGCAACCUCCGCCUCUUGGGUUCAAGCGAUUCUCCUCCCUUAGCCUCCCGAGUAGCUGGAAUUACAGCCUGUGCCACCACGCCCGGCAAAAUUUGUAUUUUUAGUAGAGACGGGGUUUCACCAUGUUGGUCAGGCUGGUUUCAAACUCCCAACCUCAGGUGAUCUGCCCACCUCAGCCUCCCAACAUGCUAGGAUUACAGGCGUGAGCCACUGCGCCCAGCCCAGGAUAAACAUUCUACCUGCCUGAAAGUACCAUAAGAGGCAAGUGAGUUUCUUGCAUGAUGGGCUUCUGCAGCUUCCCCCUCAAGUCACAUCUACCUGUUGUAUUUAUUUAUUUAUUUAUUUUUGAGACAGAGUCUCGCUCUGUUUCCCAGGCUGGAGUGCAGUGGCGUGAUCUCGGCUCACUGCAAGCUCCACCUCCCAGGUUCACGCCAUUCUCCUGCCUCAGCCUCCCAAGUAGCUGGGACUACAGGCUCCCGCCACCACGCCCGGCUAAUUUUUUGUAUUUUUAGUAGAGACGGGGUUUCACCCUGUUAGCCAGGAUGGUCUCGAUCUCCUGACCUCAUGAUCCACCCGCCUCGGCCUCCCAAAGUGCUGGGAUUACAGGCGUGAGCCACCGCGCCCGGCCCGUUGUAUCUAUUUUUUUUAGACGCAUCAAUUCAGUGUCUCUGAAGCCUUUGAUCGUUAGGAAGGUCAGUACAUAACCUCUUAGGUGAAGCUGAGUUGAUCUUUGGAGCCCAAGAGAGUUAAUUUUCAGGAGAAAAAGAAUUAGGGCAAGCUCCCCUGUGGGAUGUUAAGAGAAAGUCCAUAUGCGCUUCUUCCAUCUCUGCCUCUUGUUUUUAAAUAAGUGCUUGUGAAGUUCAGUUUAUAGAGGUUGAGUCUCAGUGCUUCCUCAGCCAGGGUGGUUUAUUGCUGUUUUACAAAGAACCAUGAACAAGCAAAAUCCUAUCAAUAGUCCUUUCUGUUUUAUGUUUUAUAGUCUUAUUUUGAAGAAUCGGCAUGGUAAAAUGAUAGACAAGUUUCAAAUAAAGCAGAUAAUUAGCUCUAGAAUUGGGGUACUUUGCCUCAGGUACAGCAUCUGUCUUGAAUACAUAGUGAUGGCUGUGUCACACAUGGGUACAUUUACUUUCCUCUCUGAUCAACUGCACCCCUUUUUACUGGCAAAGAGGGCUCCUACUUUCUACACACUUAACCAGUCAAACAGAUAGGUUUUGGCACCACCGAAAGAACCACAAGUGCACCCCAGCUGCAUCUGGGCAUGGUUUUGGUACUAGGACUAGAGAAGUGAGCAGUAAAUGACAGUCCUUACCCUAGGAAGAGAUGGGAGAAGAGAGGUGUCCAGACAUAUUUACCUUUUCUCUUCUGUCAUGCCCCAAGAACCAAGGAUCAUCUUUGAAGUGACGUCUUUUUUGUUAAAUUGGAAGAAGAAAACUUUGCAGCCAGGCGUGGUGGCUCACGCCUGUAAUCCCAGCACUUUGGGAGGCCGAGGCGGGCGGAUCACAAAGUGUCAGGAGUUUGAGAACAGCCUGGCCAACAUGGUGAAACCCCAUCUCUACUGAAAAUACAAAAUCCCAGCUACUUGGGAGGCUGAGGCAAGAGAAUCACUUGAACCUGGGAGGCGGAUGUUGCAGUGAGCCGAGAUCACGCCACUGCACUCCAGCCUGGGCAACGGAGUGAGACUCCAUCUCACAAAAAAGAGAAAAGAAAAGAAAACUUUGCUUCACUAAGUUUCUCUUGCCAUUAUCUCAUUAAUUCAGAUCUGUACCUCAUUGCUGCUCACACAUAUAUGUUUCUUACCUUAGCCUGAACCUUCUCAGGCCUUGAAGUCAUUAUUCUACUCUUUUUUUUUCUUUUCCUUUUUUAUGGCACUAGAGAAUGAAAACCUAAGGUCUUAGAAAAUCUUAACUUGAAAAAGUCUCUAACUGGCAUGAUUUGAUUACUUUUUUCCCCUGUGGACAAAUAAUUUUCUUUCCUAUAUAAUAGAUUUUUAGUAAGUGAAACCUUUGCUGCUGCUUUCCUGGGUUUACAUUAGUUUUUUCCUGCCCUUAAGAAUAAUUUAUCUGUGCUUCUCUGAUGACUGUUAAUUUCUAAUAGUGCAGGAAGGGAUGAGCUUUUGAUUUCUUCUCACUCCCCUCCUCACCCUACUUCCAAAUUACACACUAACUUCUAACCCUUACAGCCUGUUGGCACAUACACAAGAUCCACGAGACCAUGCUCCUCAGAAGCUACCCAUGUCCUUUCUCACCAUGGUGUGGCUCUUGGAGCCCUGAGUAUCUGUGACUACCCACUCCAAAGGUUGACUGUAAGAGGAGAGCGGCCUUCUUAAUUUUGCAUUUCUUAAUUUUGUUUUUCUCCAUUCCUGUUUUAUGACUUGGCCUUCAGAUGCUUCCUACUCUGGCCUCCUCCUUUUUUCUCCUAGGAAUUGUUUCCAGGUAACCUACCAUGUGCACUUCUCAGCUGCUCUGCUCACCUUUGCCCACCUUCCCGUGACCCUGAGAGUACAGAUCCGAAUAAUGUGGCCUGUGCAGAGCUCAGAGAACUGUGAGGACUACCCAUGCCUGUCAGACUCUGCUCAGGGACAGAGAUGGAUGGGUAAAUGGUGCUGUUGGAGACAUUUUUAUCUUCAUACCAGGCUCUGUUUCAUCCCUGCACCCCGCACCCCCACUCACUCCCCUGAGGGGGUAAAAUGCAGAGGUGGUUGACCUGAAGGGUCUGAUUCCCUCCUUCCCAAGCCUUAGGGCCUACCCUGGAGUGCUGCAGUGUGUGAGAGCUGCUGCUUGCUUGUUUCUCCACUAGGCCUGCUCCAAAUGCUUAGCCAAUCUCUGGAGCCGACACAGUUGCCUACGGGGUGACUUAGCACCAGGUUCCAUUAGCUCUCCAAGUGACUGUUUCCACCCAGUACUUUUGGCGCUUGAGGAUGGGGGGAGGGGGAUUAUUUAAAAUAAAUAAAAUCCGAGGUGGCAGUAGAGGAUUCCUUUUGCUUUAAAAAUCUUUGGACUAAAAAAAAAAAAAAAAAGUUUUUUAUAUAUAAAUAUAUAAAGUAAAUUGUUAUGUAACUAUUAUUGUUUCUUGUAUGUUCUAAUUUUGUUUUAUGAUGUAAUUAAAGAAAGUAAGCUGUGAA